ACCCGGCCUGUGCCAGCUUGCAGAGCUCACCAGGUGCAGACCCCUGCGGCCAGGGCGAGGACGGAUCUGAGCAGCUGGGCAGCAGGUGCCACCGCCUGUGGGACCCAGAGGGCUUGAGGACAUCUGCAAUGCUCCAGAAGCCCAAGAGCGUGAAGCUGCGGGCCCUGCGCAGCCCGAGGAAGUUCGGCGUGGCUGGCCGGAGCUGCCAGGAGGUGCUGCGCAAGGGCUGUCUCCGCUUCCAGCUCCCUGAGCGCGGUUCCCGGCUGUGCCUGUACGAGGAUGGCACGGAGCUGACGGAAGAUUACUUCCCCAGUGUUCCCGACAACGCCGAGCUGGUGCUGCUCACCUUGGGCCAGGCCUGGCAGGGCUCUGUUGGUGUCAGGGCAAGGACAAAGACCCGGGACACCUCAAGUCUGAGUCCUGGUGAUUGCCAGGCCCUGGGGAAUGGGGGAAGAUGUGGUCAGAGGCUCUUCUUGUGACCGGGGCAGGAUGUGUCUUCUGCUGGACCGGCACCUUUUGUUUGUCCCAUUGGUGGCAGAUGUGAGCGACAUCAGGCGCUUCCUCAGUGCAUUUCACGAGCCACAGGUGGGGCUCAUCCAGGCCGCCCAGCAGCUGCUGUGUGAUGAGCAGGCCCCACAGAGGCAGAGGCUGCUGGCUGACCUCCUGCACAACGUCAGCCAGAACAUCGCGGCCGAGACCCGGGCUGAGGACCCGCCGUGGUUUGAAGGCUUGGAGUCCCGAUUUCAGAGCAAGUCUGGCUAUCUGAGAUACAGCUGUGAGAGCCGGAUCCGGAGUUACCUGAGGGAGGUGAGCUCCUACCCCUCCACGGUGGGUGCGGAGGCUCAGGAGGAAUUCCUGCGGGUCCUCGGCUCCAUGUGCCAGAGGCUCCGGUCCAUGCAGUACAAUGGCAGCUACUUCGACAGAGGAGCCAAGGGCGGCAGCCGCCUCUGCACACCGGAAGGCUGGUUCUCCUGCCAGGGUCCCUUUGACAUGGACAGCUGCUUAUCAAGACACUCCAUCAACCCCUACAGUAACAGGGAGAGCAGGAUCCUCUUCAGCACCUGGAACCUGGAUCACAUAAUAGAAAAGAAACGCACCAUCAUUCCUACACUGGUGGAAGCAAUUAAGGAACAAGAUGGAAGAGAAGUGGACUGGGAGUAUUUUUAUGGCCUGCUUUUUACCUCAGAGAACCUAAAACUAGUGCACAUUGUCUGCCAUAAGAAAACCACCCACAAGCUCAACUGUGACCCAAGCAGAAUCUACAAACCCCAGACAAGGUUGAAGCGGAAGCAGCCUGUGCGGAAACGCCAGUGACACGUACACACCACGUCCUGGUCUUUGUUUGAGGCCUGACGUGGGCAUCAUUUUAACAGGUGCCUUUUUUGUUUUUUUGUUUUUCGUUUUUUUGGUCACUCCAGUAGCUCCUGGAAAAAACCUUAAAAAAUGUUUCCUCCAAAUCUGAUUUCAUUACAUUUCUGAAUUGUUGGGGUUUUUUUUGUUGUUUUGUUUUGUUUUGUAGAUGGAGUUUCACUUUUGUUGCCCAGGCUGGAGUGUAGUGGCGCGAUCUCGGCUCAGCCUCCCGAGUAGCUGGGAUUACAGGCAUGUGCCACCACGCCCGGCUAAUGUUUGUAUUUUUAGUAGAGACGGGGUUUCACCAUGUUGGUCAGGCUGGUCUCAAACUCCUGACCUCAGGUGAUCCGCCCACCUCAGCCUCCCAAAGUGCUGGGAUGACAGGUGUGAGCCACUGCGCCCAGCCUGAAUCAUUUCUUAUACCUUCUGACAGCCCAACUUCCAGAGGACAGCUCUGGGGUACUCGUUGGAUGUCUGUGAGUACCUGGUCAUACGGGUCAGUAGGGAUAAGAAUUGUCUCUGGGCUGAGGAAUUCUUCUGUUCUCUGGUUUCACCAGCGUUGGGUUUGCUCAUGUAAUGUGGUCACCAUACUCAAAUGGUGUCAUGGCUGAAGUUGGCCACCUUGCUUGAGGGACAAGUUGUUUAUGUAUCAGCUCUCUGCUGGGUCUCCCUUUCCAUGGCAAAUGGGCAGCUCCAUCCUCUUGACUCUUCUAAAUGCCCAAAAGAGGUGUCAUGCUUUGGGGGUACGAUGUUUAUACUCCGUAAAGAACAUACAAGGACAUUCACUGCUGAUUUUUUUUUUUGUUUGUUUGAGACAGGGUCUCACUCUGUCGCUCAGGCUGGAGUGCAGUGAUGCAAUCUUGGCUCACUGCAACCUCCGCCUCUCAGGUUCAAGUGGUUCUCCUUCCUCAGCCUCCCAAGUAGCUGGGAUUACAGGCACCUACCACCAGGGCCAGCUAAUUUUUGUAUGUUUAGUAGAAACGGGGUUUCACCAUGUUGGCCAGGCUGUUCUCGAACUCCUGACCUCAGGUGAUCUGCCCGCCUCGGUCUCCCAAAGUGCUGGGAUUACAGGCAUGAGCCACUGCACCUGACCUGCUGAAUUGUUUAUAAUGGCAAGAAAUAGGAAACCCCCCAAUGUCUGUUGAACAGCUAUCACGUUGAACCACGUGAAACUGCUGUUUUCUAGGCCAAAAAUGGUGAGCGAUCAUUUAUUUCAUGAUUCAACCUGAUACAUUUACAUAGUGCAAAACUGUGUCACAGUUUCAGGCUUUUAUGAGGAAAGCGUUUCUGUGUAGAAACUGGAAGCUGUUCAGGGCAUCGGCAGCUGAACCCUGCUCCGUUGGUCAGCGUUACUAUCAUCUCGGAUCAUAUGGAGCUCAUGUCAGCCGUGUGGGUGGCGGGUGCACAGAGACGGUCUGGAAGGAAACACGCGGAUCUGAACAGCAGUAAUCCUGGGGGAUACGGGGGUUGGGCUAGAUUACAGAGGGCUCAUUUUCUACGUCAUGUAUUUUAUGAUACUUGAAUUUUUUGAAAUGGGCAUUUAUUUUAUAACAUGUUAAAAUGUACUUUUUAAAUUAAGUCAUUUUGUAAUAUUUGAAUUUUUACAUUUGUUGUACAAUCAGGAAAAGCAAUAAAGAUUUUUCAAAAAUAGA